CCCUUUCCCUCAGCCUCCCGGGAGCGUGACGCGGCGGCCCGGGGGCCUCCGGGCGCCUUCCGGGGCACGCGGGUGAGGAACUGGGAAGCGGGGGAAAUCGGCGCCACGGCGGUCGAUUAGCACCGAAACAGAGUGAUGGGCGCGGAGCGUCCCUGCACACACACACACACUCACACACACACACACACGACCCCUGCGGCCACGGGAGGGGAGAGCCGGGGUCGGCUCCGCGAGCGCAGGGUGGCGCUUGUCUCCUCCUGCUUGCCGUAGGAAGUGGACGCUGGAAGCCCGAGGAGCCGCUUCGUGUCUUCCCAAACCUAAGCGGCGCCCCACCCCCUACUUCUCGUGGCCCGUUACGCCCGGGGCAGCCAAGCGCCGCGGGAGCAGCGCCGGGAUCGACCCUGGCUGCUGGGGGGACGCUUUGUCCCAAGAAAGCUGGUUUUUUGCCCCUUAGCUUCGUGGAACGCGGCCGCGAAAUUAGUGGUCUUCUGACCUGAGACUCGCGGGGCUGCGCACACGGGCAUCGCCGAGGACCCCAGCAAUGGACGUCGUGUCUGUGGUGAUCCCGCCAGGACGCGGGGAGCGUGGGCGGAAAUUAGUGUCCACGUUCCGACCCUGCGCUGUGCCAAACGCUGCUUCGGGAGCUGUUUAUUUAGCCUCCGACAGCUAAGCGAAUCGGCGGGCGGCUGGGGCCUGGUGCAACCCGAUUUUCUCGUGCAGACUCGCAGCCGGCUUUGGUUUUGUUUUUUGUUUUUUGUUUUUUUUUUGGAGCCAUGCAGAGGGUAGCUACAGCCAUUAAUUUAAGGAUGUAGAUAAGCUAUCUCUAAACCAAGAAAGAUCGACAUGCACUUGGAUCAUUGCAGUUUCUGGGCCUGCUGUCAUCUCCCCCUUCAGUACUUCCCACAUAUGACUACCAACUGUUAGACGAUGUGCUGCUGCCAGACCAGCCUUUCAUUUCUUGGACAUCCGGCUAUUUACCCAGGAAAAGUCAUCCUUUGACUAUUUUUCAUGACCUUUCUCAUCUGACUCGUGAUCUGCCCAUCUUGUUACUCCCUAGCAGUGUGGUAAGAGGUCAACCAGAAUCAAGAUGUCUGGGACUGAGGAAGCAAUUCUUGGAGGACGUGACAGCCAUCCUGCUGCUGGCGGCGGCUCAGUGUUAUGCUUUGGACAGUGCCAGUACACAGCAGAAGAGUACCAGGCCAUCCAGAAGGCCCUGAGGCAGAGGCUGGGCCCAGAAUACAUAAGUAGCCGCAUGGCUGGCGGAGGCCAGAAGGUGUGCUACAUUGAGGGUCAUCGGGUAAUUAAUCUGGCCAAUGAGAUGUUUGGUUACAAUGGCUGGGCACACUCCAUCACGCAGCAGAAUGUGGAUUUUGUUGACCUCAACAAUGGCAAGUUCUACGUGGGAGUCUGUGCAUUUGUGAGGGUCCAGCUGAAGGAUGGUUCAUAUCAUGAAGAUGUUGGUUAUGGUGUUAGUGAGGGCCUCAAGUCCAAGGCUUUAUCUUUGGAGAAGGCAAGGAAGGAGGCGGUGACAGACGGGCUGAAGCGAGCCCUCAGGAGUUUUGGGAAUGCACUUGGAAACUGUAUUCUGGACAAAGACUACCUGAGAUCACUAAAUAAGCUUCCACGCCAGUUGCCUCUUGAAGUGGAUUUAACUAAAGCGAAGAGACAAGAUCUUGAACCGUCUGUGGAGGAGGCAAGAUACAACAGCUGCCGACCGAACAUGGCCCUGGGACACCCACAGCUGCAGCAGGUGACCUCCCCUUCCAGACCCAGCCAUGCUGUGAUACCGGCGGACCAGGACUGCAGCUCCCGAAGCCUGAGCUCAUCCGCCGUGGAGAGCGAGGCCACGCACCAGCGGAAGCUCCGGCAGAAGCAGCUGCAGCAGCAGUUCCGGGAGCGGAUGGAGAAGCAGCAGGUUCGAGUCUCCACGCCGUCAGCUGAGAAGAGUGAGGCAGCGCCUCCGGCCCCUCCUGUGACGCACAGCACUCCUGUAACUGUCUCAGAACCACUCCUGGAGAAAGACUUCCUUGCAGGAGUGACUCAAGAAUUAAUCAAGACUCUUGAAGACAACUCUGAAAAGUGGGCUGUGACUCCCGAUGCAGGGGAUGGUGUGGUCAAGCCCUCGUCUAGAGCAGACCCAGCCCAGACCUCUGACACAUUAGCCUUGAACAACCAGAUGGUGACCCAGAACAGGACUCCACACAGCGUUUGCCACCAGAAACCACAAGCAAAAUCUGGAUCUUGGGACCUCCAAACUUAUAGCGCUGACCAACGCACAACAGGAAACUGGGAAUCUCAUAGGAAGAGCCAGGACAUGAAGAAAAGGAAAUAUGAUCCAUCUUAACUGAGGCUCAGGCCACAUAAUUGGACUCUGUCACAAAGGGACUUUGGAAAACUACUUUUUGGUCAUGAAAUUGUUCAUCGCUGCUGGAGAAUGAACGUCAUUGCGAUUUAUCUUGCUUCAUUCUGAACCUUAUCAAGAGGAUCUGACUGAGAGCCCACUGCAGUUAGAGCUGAGCACUUUUGAAAAGCUUGUCCAUCACUCUAGUAGGGAGAGGCUCUGGACAGAUGAAUACCUUUUCUUCGGCUUGUGAGGCUUCCCACUAUUUAUUACUGAACUAUUAUGUUAAUGAAGAUGGACAUUUUAGGAAUCACCAAUGGCUCCUUGCCCUCAAGCAAUAUAGGCCAGACUUGGUCCUAAGCACCUGCCUCAGCAAUUGUCUACAUUCAGUUGUUUUGCAUAACGUCUGCCUUCUUUCCUUUACGGUCCAUGCCUUUAAUGUUGCCCACAUUAAGCACUGUGGAUCACGACAGGAAAAAGGUUGGAGCAGUGCUUUUCACUACUUUGUAUCAAUCCAGGCUACAAUCUUCAUUUAAUAUAAAUAAUUUAUGGAUUUAUGACAUUACAAUCCUGCAUUGUUUCAAGACUGACAUUUUUUCCUAAGGAAGGAAAUAAUCAUCUAAGACCACGAAAAAAGGCUGUUUUUUGUUUUUUUUUUUUUUUUUUUUUUUGAGACGGGGUCUGGCUGUGUUGCCCUGACUGGAGUUCAGUGGUGCAAACACAGCUCUCUCCACAACCUCUUGGGCCCAAGUGAUACUCCCACCUCUGCCUUACAAAAUACAGGGAUUACUGGUGUGAGCCACUGUGUCUGGCCAGAAAAGGCAUUUUUGAGAAAGCAAAUCGUAUACCUUAUUAACAAAAUAGAAUAUAUAUAUAUUGCUUAUCUGAAAUGCUUGAAACCAGAAUUGUUUUGCAUUUUUUGAAUAUUUGUAUACACAUAAUGAGACCUUGGGGAUGGGACCCAAGUCUGAACGUGGAAUUCACCUGUGUUUCGUGUAUAUGCCUCAUACACAUAAUUUUGUGCAUGAAACAGAGUUUUUGUAUAAGAAGAUACACUGCAGCUGAAGAGGGCUGGGUUUUUUUUUCUCUUAGGGUCGCUGCAUAAACUGUUGUAUGCCUGGUGCUUUGCGACUUGUCACACGAGGUCACGUGUGGAAUUUUCCACUUCUGGCAUCACGUCAGUGCUCAGAAAUUUUCUGAUCUCAGAGCAUUUCAAUUAGGGAUGCUCAAACGCAACUGUUUCUACUUCCCCAUUUCAGGUGUGAGAUGUAACCCACCUUGACCAUAAAUUGGCUUUUCAUAGUGCUCAGAUGUUUCAUAAUUCUUCCCCCAAAAUAAUGAAGUUUGCAGUUUAACAACUUUUUUUUUGAGAGGGGGGGUCUGGCUCUGUAGCGCAGGCUGGAGUGCAGCGGUGCCAUCUUGACUCAUUGCAGCCUCCGCCUGCCAGGAUUCAAGCAAUUCUCCUGCCUCAGGCUCCCGAGUAGCUGGGAUUACAGACACCCACCACGACGCCCGACUAAUUUUUGUAUUUUUAGUAGAGGAGACGGGGUUUCUCCAUGUUGGCCAGGCUGGUCUCAAACUGACCUCAAGUGAUCUGCCCACCUCGGCCUCCCAAAGUAAAAAGUACUAGAAUUAUAGGCAUGAGCCAUUGCGCCCAG